GCUUUUAUCUCGGAGCCGCGUCGCUUCGUGCGCUGCCAGCGGGGCUCAGCCAGUCGGCUGGAAUUGAGUAGCAUUCAUUGAAUCUGCGGAUUUCAUGACGUCUCUCUGCGUGGUCCACCACUUUUCUCCUAACCGGGGAUUUUUUUUUUCUUCUGCCACUCUUAUCUUUCCCCACUUCAUUCCACCCAGUCUCCCUCCCCCGUCCCUGCCCAAACGCGCGCCCCUCCGCCCCUCCCUUGGCCCCAGCGCCCAGCCCUGCUCUCCGCGCUCGGCCAGAGGGAGCCAGUCCGGAGACGGCCGCACCUGGCUGGAGAGGCUGGGCGGGCGGAGGGGUGGAGACCCGCGGACGCCGGGAAGCCGGACCUGGAGCCGGAGCAGCCGCGAGCAGAAUGGAGUCUCCUAACAGCCUCUCGGUGCUGAUGUGAAAUUUGACCAUCUGAUUCCAGUUUUUUUCUUUUCCUUUUCUUUUUUGCAUUUCCUUCCCUCGCCAUCCGUCGUGUAGUGAAUUGUUCAGUCUUGCUCCGUUUCAAGAGAGGAGAUCAUGAUUGAGUGAAGCCACCCCGUCCGCAGCCAGGAAAAGCACAAAGAAGAAACUGCAACAAUGGCCAAGCUGACAGAAUCCAUGACUAACGUCCUGGAGGGCGACUCCAUGGAUCAGGACGUCGAAAGCCCAGUGGCCAUUCACCAGCCAAAGUUGCCUAAGCAGGCCAGGGAUGACCUGCCAAGACACAUCAGCCGAGAUCGGACCAAAAGGAAAAUCCAGAGGUACGUGAGGAAAGACGGAAAGUGCAAUGUUCAUCACGGCAACGUGAGGGAGACCUAUCGCUACCUGACCGAUAUCUUCACCACAUUAGUGGACCUGAAGUGGAGAUUCAACCUAUUGAUUUUUGUCAUGGUUUACACAGUGACCUGGCUCUUUUUUGGAAUGAUCUGGUGGUUGAUCGCAUACAUACGGGGAGACAUGGACCACAUAGAGGACCCCUCCUGGACUCCUUGUGUUACCAACCUCAACGGGUUCGUCUCUGCUUUUUUAUUCUCAAUAGAGACAGAAACCACCAUUGGUUAUGGCUACCGGGUCAUCACAGAUAAAUGCCCAGAGGGAAUUAUUCUUCUCUUAAUCCAAUCUGUGUUGGGGUCCAUUGUCAAUGCAUUCAUGGUGGGAUGCAUGUUUGUAAAAAUCUCUCAACCCAAGAAGAGGGCAGAGACCCUGGUCUUUUCCACCCAUGCAGUGAUCUCCAUGCGGGAUGGGAAACUGUGCCUGAUGUUCCGGGUAGGGGACCUUAGGAAUUCCCACAUUGUGGAGGCUUCCAUCAGAGCCAAGUUGAUCAAAUCCAAACAGACCUCGGAGGGGGAGUUCAUCCCGUUGAACCAGACGGAUAUCAACGUAGGGUAUUACACGGGGGAUGACCGUCUGUUUCUGGUGUCACCGCUGAUCAUUAGCCAUGAAAUUAACCAACAGAGUCCUUUCUGGGAGAUCUCCAAAGCCCAGCUGCCCAAAGAGGAACUGGAAAUUGUGGUCAUCCUAGAAGGAAUGGUGGAAGCCACAGGGAUGACAUGCCAAGCUCGAAGCUCCUACAUCACCAGUGAGAUCCUGUGGGGUUACCGGUUCACACCUGUCCUGACCCUGGAGGACGGGUUCUACGAAGUUGACUACAACAGCUUCCAUGAGACCUAUGAGACCAGCACCCCAUCCCUUAGUGCCAAAGAGCUGGCCGAGUUAGCCAGCAGGGCAGAGCUGCCCCUGAGUUGGUCUGUAUCCAGCAAACUCAACCAACAUGCAGAACUGGAGACUGAAGAGGAAGAAAAGAACCUCGAAGAGCAAACAGAAAGAAAUGGUGAUGUGGCAAACCUGGAGAAUGAAUCCAAAGUUUAGUGCCCUAGCUGGGCAAACCCUUCUCUUCUCCCCCCAACACAAUCUUUCCUUGUCUCUCAUUCUCUUUCUUUUUCUGUCUCUCUUGCUUUGUUCUUUAUUUGUUUAUAUUUAAUUUUUACAUGACCAGAAAACAAAUCUUCAAGGUGUAAAAUAUCUACCUGCCCUCUCUCAGUUAUUCAGAUUGACAAGGUAGACAUGGAUUUGAUGAAAGUGCAAAGUGCCCUCAUUUGUGGCCCAAGCCUGGUCUCCUCCCAAAAUACUACACAUCCAACUCCUGGAGAUUUCAGUUACUUACCUGCAUGUGUUGUACAAUACCAGAUCACUCAAAAAGGUGUGUCAAAGAUUUUACCUGGGAUAUGACAAGCAAGGUUUCUGGUGCCUAUUUAUUCAUUCAGUGAGACACAGAGUGGAGCCCUCAGUUUUAUGGAUCCCAAUUCAUUUCAUCUACUACAGGGUGAGGUGCUUGCCCCCAUGUGGGUGUGGCAGUUACAGGGCCCAGGUGAGCUGAAGACAAACCACUGUACAUAUAUAUGCCUUAUGUAAUUAUUUUCUUUUUGUAAUUAGUAAUAAAACCCAGCAUGUACAAAAGUACCAUAGAACAGAACUGCUAAAUACUGUACAUAGAUGUAUCAUUAAUGUAGGUUUAGAUAUAUAACUUUAGAAAUAAGAAGCAAAAAAAAAAAGAAAGAAAGAAAGAUUCCUAACAUGCAGUAGGCAUUUCUGUUUUGAUGUCUGUGUUUUCCAGGUUAUUUUGAUCCAGUUGACGGCUGGCCCUUCAGUGCAUGGCCUUUGUUUGUGUCUCAGACUGGCAGACGUUAGGGUACCUCACUGUUCCCACACGGAUCCUUUCAUUGAAUCCAACAAGCCAUAGGUCUGGGGGAAAUUGAGAGGUCUGGUAGAUGGCAAAACCCACCACCAAUAUGCUGAUAUACUGUGAAAUGUUACAAAACAGAUGUCUUUUUUUAAAAGAUAACAAGGGCCUCACUAACUGGCCUGGAGGAGGGGGAAUACCAGGAAGGAAAUAUUCUCUAGCCUGUCACCAAAGGUAUGUUUUUACUUUUCACAUGAGCUCUUGCCCUUUGUAGUACAAUAAUUUAGGAAACUUUUCUGCAAAACCAUUGAUUCUCCAGCUGUAGUUUCUCUACACUCUUACAAUGAGACAUGGUAAGUUAGCAGAAGAUGGUUUGGGUCUAAAGCCGUGAAAUUCACAAAGGCAUGUAGUGAGUGGCAUGCAUUAUAAUCAUCGACCUCUCACUUUGACUCUAUCUGGCUUUCUGAGAAUGACAUCUCGCCUGUCCCUGGGGCUUAUCCAUCAGCAUUUCUUGCAUUGUGAUCUUUUAUUAUUUUGAAAUGACCAGAGUUCAGUAUUCAAAGAUUAGAUCAACAAUCUUGAUGAUUGUCUAAGAAAUGUCUCUAGAGUAUGCCACAGGCUAGAAAUCAAAUCCAGUGUCUGUCAAUCAAAAGAAAACAAAUAAAAAAAUUCCAGCCUUAAUUCACUUUAAUCUGCAAAAAGGAAAGAAGGGAGGAAGGGAGGGAGGAAGGAAGGAAGGAAGGAAGGGUAUUUGUACUGGAAAUCUGAAUUUUAAAAUGAAAAAAAUAAGGAAACAAAUCUUAGAUCAAACCUCCGGGGCAGGUGGAGAUUUUGCACUGUUACAGAUCUUUCACAUUCACUUUGCAUUUAUAAGCUGUUUGUUCUUUAACACAGUUGCCCAUCAUAAAUAUUCAUUGAAUGGAUCCAAGUUUAUUUUCAGCUCCUACAGCUGUGCUCAGUUUGAGGCUCUGCACCAUGGAGGUCAAAGAGAUCAAACUAGCUGUCCCUCUUUGUUUCCCUUGCCUUCCCUGACCUGAUCGCACAGGCCUUUGGUGUAGUCUGGGGACCUUGUCUACUAAAAAAGAAGUCCCAGGAUAAGGAAAGUGGCUCCUAAAUAUAACCUCGGGGCCUCUCUUCUCCCAUCUCAGAGACCUUGGAUCAGGACAACUGCCUCUUGGCACUGACUUUAAGGAAAACAAAACUGUUGGCUAUAGCCCUUUCCUGUUUGCCAGCAUUUCCUUUUUUGCAUUGAAUCUCUGUUGAAUCAUUUCUUUAUUUCGCACACUCUAAGAAGGAGGUGGUGGUCCGGGAGGAGGAAGCUCGAUACACUCCCCUUGAGGCUGCGGGGAGGAGCCAUGGCUUGACCUCUCUGCAGCCUAAUGAAGGGCACUCUUGGCUUGGGGAGCUCCCCUGCAACCUUGCCAGGGUCGCAGGGCAGGCCAUGGCAGGCACAAAACAAGAUGGAAUAGGGGCGGCAAAAUGUCUUCUAAUUUAGCUCUUGAAGACUCACUGGGCCUUUUUAAUUCCAUUGCUAAGGUUUAAAGGACAGCGCACACCCCCGUGUCUGGUUGGAAGAGCAAGCAGCUCAGGGCCUCAUCCCUGCUUGCCUGCCCUUUAGCACAACUGAACGAAGAGCCUUGACAACACGUUGGCCACGUGCACCUGUCAGUUCUGUGUCUGUGACGGGCACCCAGAUGUGAGGUCUCUCCCUGUUUCUCACUGUCUUUGUUGUCAAUGUAGUUGGAGACAGAACUUGAACCAAAUCUCGUUUUUGUAAUGUGAGCCUCUGAAUCUUUACAUGGGGAUGCUCCUGAAGAACCUUUUACUAGAAUGUCCCUAUCAAACAUGUCUAUUUUUCUACAGUUGUUAACACAGUUUAACAGUGUAUUUUGUGUCAACUGUUAAAAUUUGGAACUGAAAGUUCAUUGAGACUGAUUUUCUAAGCAGCGAGUAGUGAGUGAAUGGUGUUUUCCAUUAAGACAGCUCAACAAAAUUGACCCCACAAUUUCCACUCAUUCUAUUCCGCAAUAUCCAGUCCUCAUUCCCUCAGUCACUCCAUUAGCAAACCAAGUGCAAUGAGAAUUUUUUAAAAGUCUCUUUUAAUACAACAGUAUCCAUAACUAAUGAAGAUCACUCUCAACUAGAUCCUUUGGUCUGUUUGGUUAAUGUAUUUGAGUCAUUUUUCCAUAAAGCAUGGUGGGAUCCGUGAGCCAGAUAAGAAUUUGGAAUUUAAGGGUUAUGGUUUGCCACAGUUGACCCCAAUUUGACAGAACAAAGUGCUCCUGGAUGGAAGGGCAGGUUCAGCUGCAAGCAUGACCCCCCACCACAAGGCUGCUGAGUUCCUCGGAUUCUCACCUCCACCCACCCCAACGUGCUCUCCAACUGGAAGAGCACCCAUUCAUUUAUAAAUCAACUUUAUGGAACCAAUAAAAUCAUUUCUGUUUUAGCUGUCCCCUGGGUAAGCUAUACUCUUUUACAUUAACAUAGCAAAUGUCAACUUUUCUGUUCCUUCAAACAUGGCCUUCCAGCCUGGUUGUUCCAGCAUAUAUCCCCUCUAUGUCCAUGAGGCAGAACUCUCUCUUCCCCCACUCCGUUCUUCCAUCUAUCCCCAUCCUUUGCUGUUUCCCUGGUUCUCCAGUUCCAAUUCUAUUGUUUUAGUUCAGUACCUUAUGUUCCCUAACAGAAAUCCAGCUGCAAAUGUCAACCUAUUUCUUAAGCACAAUUUUCUCUUGCAGGUCUAACCAAGCUAGGGCUCUGAAAUGUCUAUUUUUCACUGCACUCCAAUUUAAAAAUUAUUCAUGACUUCAUUUAAUAGUCUAAAUUUUGAAUUCUCCAGAGCAACAUUCUUAUGCUUUCCAUCCCUACAUUUUCUUACAUUUCAGUUUUCUUACUUUUUUCCCCUUUGCUUUUUUAUUUAGAUUUAAGCCAGUGUCUUUGGGAUAUUUAGAAACUGCUUACAAAGGUGGGAACUGGUGGACAGAGAAAGGGGGCAUAAGAAUGCUAUUAGAAAACUACCUGAACUCACCAGAAGAAUGGGAAAUCAUUUGAUUUGCUGAGAGAAUACAAUUAAAAUACUCAUAGUAAAUCAUUUCCAAAACAGUUUGCUAAUAGUCUGGCUACUCUUCAGUCUUUCUUUCCUUGACUUGGGUGAUACUCUGUAUGAUUUAAAAAUGUCAGGAAGGUAGUUGAAAGUUCAGUGUCCUCUAUAUAUUGUAAACAUUAUCUUCAAGGAUGAUUUCCUUUCAAUGGAUGGCUUUAACAUUGAAAAACAUAGGUAACAUAUACAUAAUAGAUGAUUCAUUGAUAUUACUUUACAAUACACUAAAAUAACAUUAUCUUGUUUCUGAACUUUAUGGCCAACCGGUAUCUAAGAAAAUGUUAGCCUUUAAUUUAAAAUUGAGUAAAGCACGCCUCUUCCUAAUAUUUCUGCCUUUAAUGUCUUGAGUGCUUUAGAUGCAGAGUGUCAUCUAGAAGUCAAAAUUCUGUCAGAAGGCUGCUAAGAGAUUUUGAUAAAUCACAGAAUAUAUAAUAAUAACCCAACAAUAUUUUACCCAACAUGGUGUGGUGUUUGAGAGCAUUAAGAGCACUUGUACAAAUUAUCUUAUUUCAUUCUAAUUCACCAUGAGAGGUUGAGUAUUAUAAUUUACAUUUUAUAGAGGGAAAACUAGGGUUUGGGCAAAUUGGCCAAGUUUAAAGGCCAGUGAAUCAUAGCUCCUUGUCUCAAAUCCAGGUCACAGGGCCCUAAGCUGUGGGCUAUUUUUACUACAAAAAAUUUCAGCAAACCAAAUCUGCUAAAAAAAAAAAAAUCUGGCCUGCUGCCUGUUAUUGUACCACUUGUGAGCUAAGAGCAAUUUUUACAUUUUUUAAUAAUUGGGGGAAAAAAAAGAAAAGAAGAAUAUUUUGAGACAUGUGAAAAUCAUCCUAAAUUCAAAUUUCAAUGUCCACAAACAAAGUUUUAUUGGAACACAGCCACAGCCAUUUGUCUGUGUAUUGCCUAUGGCUGCUUCCACAUGCACUCACAGAGCUGAGUAAUUACAACAGAGACCGUGUGGCCAGCAAAGAUUGAAAUAUUUACUAUCUGGCCCUGUAUAAAAAAAGUUUGCUGACCCCUGUACUGUACUGUUAAGUACUAUUGGUACUAUUAAGUACUAGUAAUAGUACUAUUAAUAAUAGUAUGUAAGAGUACUAAGUACUAUGAAAUAUUGUACUGUACUCUUAAGAGAGUCCUAGGCAAUAUAGAAGAAUGACUUUUUUUCUAGCAUAAAUUAUUGAAGUCACUCAUAAGUCUGUUCAAAAUAACAUAACUCUUUUUUUUCGGUUGUCAAAGAGACAACUGCUUCACAAGACUUAGAGAGCCCAGUCAUUCAGUUAGGGUCUCAAAGGAAGAAUCCUUCCUUUUCAUGCCAUUCCUCCAGAGUGGCAAAUAGAGUCAACAGCCAGCCAGGAUCUAGCGGUCAACUCAGAAAGUGGAUACAGUAAAAUUACUCCUUAAUGAACUACAGAGAAAUGGGCAUUCCCAGCCCAGCCGCUGAAAUAUUGCUUCAGUGGCACCCUCAGGCGUUGGAUGAUGUACAUAGCUCAGGCUGCCAGUCUCUGCUCAGCAAAGCAGCCCAGACCUGCAGUGGUUGCCACACAUCAAACCCGCCUCGCUCCUCCACAUGGCUUCUCUCUUAGGCUCUCUUGGAGGAGAGUUAAAUAGGUGGCCCAGAUGUCUCCCUCUGUUUUCUUGCUAGUUUUCUCUAGCCUACAGUUUACAACUGAUCAAGGUGAUGAACGUGAACCUGGAACUAGCUCAUGUUUAAUUGCGCUAGUUUUUGCUCUCUCUAGCCACUAAGCUAGAAGUUUAAUGUGUAAUUAAAGAACUAAAUGCUUCUUAUGGAAAACCAAAAGGUCCUUUGAAAAGAGCUCAGGGAGACACGGAAGUAUAGUAAAGGGUUGUUGGAUUUCUUGCGCUUUCUGAGUCUGAAGCAAAGACAAAGAUUGGUAAUUACAGACAUAAUGGAUGGAAAAAGUCCAGACCUUGGGGUUUUUAGAUGAGUCAAUAUUAAAUGGCAUUCUUUGUGUCACUAAGCUGAACUCCCUUGUCUUCUAAGGAAGCAUUUCUAAUGCCAGAGGUAGUCAGCCAAGCUAGGUUCCUUAUCUUUUUAGUUCUAUGGAAAAACAUAUCAAGUUCUCUUAUGAGUGCUUUCCUGGAAAUCAGAUGAGAAAGAAAAAAAAGUAACAAUGUAACAAAUCAUUGUGAUGUUGUUAUAUUGUCGACAGAUAAAGGAUGGAUUUGAUCCUGCGUCUGAAACUAAGUAGGUAAUGGUAUCUACAAUAUAGAUCAUGCAAAAAGCUUGUGACCCUUCAACUGCAUGGAAGAGUGGGAGGAAACAACUAAGUGGGAGGAAACAAAUCUCAAAGUUCAACACCAUAAAACUUAAAUAAAUGUAAAAGGAGUCAAACUUUUACUUGGCCUCAUUGCCUUGGUAAAAGAAAGCUUCAUGUAUCCACCUAAUUCAAUAAGAGAGUCCUAGGAAAAGGAAGGCAAAAUACUUUAAAGGCACACAAAAAUAUUUCACUGGGGUGGUCAACAUGAUUAAGUGAUGGAGAUUAGAUUUAUCACUGAUGAAAACAGUAUUUAUAGAGUUAUUUUUAGACACUAUACCCCCUAGAUGCAAAUCCCAACAUGCACUGUGGUUGGCCGGAGAAUUGUGGCCACAUAGUAAACAGAUCUUGAUUUCAGAGAAUGAAAUGUUCCUACCGACUUUGUGUAAUUGCCCAUUUCAAGAUUAAGGCUCAGUGCCCAUUGUUUUAACACCGAUCAUCAAUACUGUGAUAUCAACUAAGCCAAUCUUUAUAAGAAUAUGAAGGGCUGUUUUUCUCAGGCAAUGUAAAUAUCUGCUACCAACAAGCACUAGUGAAAUAAACAUGUAAUCAUCAUCGUUUCUAAAACUCUGAUAGAAAUCACAAAACAUUCAAGCAAAAGGGCAAGGUCUUCCAGGAGCCUAGGAGCAGACUUUUGGCUACAAAGAGCCUAGUCCAGGCUGAAUGCCUUAUGGAGUAUGUCAGUCUUGGGUCUUAUCACUAAACACAACUAGUAGAACUCGAUCAACUGGAGUGCAGAGAUCAGAGUUUCGGUCAGCCGUGCAUUACCCAAACCUCUGGGUCUUCAGCCAGUCUUCUUAGAAGAGGGGAAGGAGCACUGUCCUCAGAUCCGGCCAUCACGGGCAUCGCCCUGACAUCAUCUCUCAGCAUUGCUGACUGUGGGCAUGGGUAUGAGAAAUACCCUCCCGUAGCUCAGACUUGGGCAGAACAAAAUCCUCAGCCAUGCCCACCCACUGAGGUCUCUCUAGGGGAGCUUCUCCCUGCAGGGUCUGGCUCUUGCCCAUCUGGACAAUGACCCCCUAGAAGUAUCUUCCGGGGGACCCUGUAUCUUUCAAGCUUAACUUGCCCCACACCCUUGACCCCACAGAGCACCUCCCUGGGUCAGGAAUGAUGACUAAAUUAAGACCUUUAGCAUCUGCUAAGCACAGGGGUGCCCUCCCAUGUGAAAGUCCAAGUAAAAUAAAUGGAGUCAGGGUAAGGAAAUCCCCAAAAGUUCUGAUUUUCUCAUGGUGAUGAUCUCAGUGCUUUUCUUUUUCAUGACAUAUCUAAUUCUCUUUUCUCUAGGAAGUCUCACGUUUUGGUAUCACGAUGCCGUGGGCACAGACUCAGUCAUCGGGCCAAUGGCAGAACUCUCUCCAGAUAGUCUGACCUGGUCCCUCUUUUUGAGUAAGGCUGGGAGUUUGGUUUGUUUGAGCCACCCCACAACCAAUAGAAUCCCACCCUGGCUAAGAAAUCUCACAAGGCCGGGUGCUGUGGCUCACACCUGUAAUCUCAGCACUUUGGGAGGCCAAGGUGGCAGAUCACCUGAGGCCAGGAGUUUGAGACCAGCCUGGCCAAUAUGGUAAUACCCCGCCUCUACUAAAAAUAUGAAAAAGUUAGCUGGGCAUGGUAGUUCCUGCCUGUACACCCAGCUACUCUGGAGGCUGAGGCACAAGAAUAGCUUAAACUUGGGAGGGGGAGGUUGCAGUAAGCUGAGAUCAUGCCACUGCACUCCAGCCUGGGCCACGGAGCGAGACUCAGUCUCAAAAAAAGAAAGAAAAGAAGGAAGGAAGGAAGGAAGGAAGGAAGGAAGGAAGGAAGGAAGGAAGGAAAAAAGAUAAAGAAAGAAGGAAGGAAGGAAGGAAAGAAAGAAGGAAGGAAGGAAGAAGGAAAGAAAGAAAGAAAAGAAAGAAAGAAAAAGAAAGAAAAGAAAAGAAAAGAAAAGAAAAGAAAGAAAGAAAGAAAGAAAGAAAGAAAGAAAGAAAGAAAGAGAAAAGAAAGAGAAAGAAAGAAAGAGAAAAGAAAUCGCACAUCCCCACCUCUAUCAGGGUCACCAAAUGAAGGCAUCAAUUUCAAGUCCCGUUAUUAUCUGCAAGGAACUCUGCAUUGCAGCACUUACAGACACAACUUAUGCUGUCUCCUGGUGCCCACACAGCUUUCGGGUGAUGGCAGAUUGUCAGCCAACCAUUCCCCCCAGCUGCUCUCUCUUAAUUUGCUCCCUCAUCUCACCACGAAAACUUCACUUUUCCUGGCACCCCCGUUGGAAGGUUAAUAUCAUUUUUGAGCAUCCACAAUCCAGCAACCUAUUAUUGGGGUUAGUCCUAUUCCUUACCACUUAAUAGCCACCACCAAUUUUAACCGAGCGUAUAUGUUCAGAGUCUAACCAUAUAUAUAUAUAUAUAUAUAUAUAUGUACAUUUUGUUCCUGCUUCAUAAUUGCCCAGAGAGUCUAUGAGUGAUGGUUGGGCGUAUACAUGGUCUCAGCCCGGUAACUGACGAGAGCAGCAUAAAGUUAGGUCUUGUGCUGAAAGGACAGCUGGACUGGUCCAGUGGGAUCUUCUUGUCCUUUGCAGCAUGCCAUUAGGGGACCAGCUUGCCAAAGAAGCUCCUGAACAUCUUUAUUCAGCCCAGUGCUUCCUCGUCUUAACCAAGAGCCACACAGAGACAACAGUGAACUCACAAGUUCAUAGGAUUCCAAAAUGAUUGACUCCCCAAGUGUCUGCCUGUGUUGGCAAAGUGCUCUUUCCUUUCCCACUGUCUGCACAGACUGUACUCUGGGGAAACUCCCAGCACUUGUGGGUGCCUGGUUACCGAGGAUGUGCUUGGCUGCCAUGGUAACUCCCAGCCUCUCAGUGUGGACCACUCUCCCGCAGGCUCGAGGAGACCUGGCAGAGGCCCCAUGGGGCGGAGGCUCCCUAGGGCUGCUCCACCUGCAGACAGCCUUGGGAGAACCCAAGGUAAUGUGGAGUAGGACCCAGCACACAGGAGCUCCCUCCGCACGCCAGGUCUGGGGUAUUCCCAUCCUUUCUUCCUAAGAUGGGAUGCACUUAGGUGGCCAAAUUGCUUCUUAAAAGGCUCUUCUUCAAGCCAUCAUCCUCAUAUCACACUCAUGCCCACACUCCAGUCACAUUUGCCUUUAAAAAAUUUUCAAAAUUAUUUUUGUAUUAUCCCAUGUAACAGAUGUCCAAAGAGUUGCCAUUUUCUUAACACUAAAUAAAUUCUGCCUAGAAGAUUAAGAUUGGUCCAGAACAGGGAGUGUUUUAAUAAGCACAAAUAUAAACAAAAGCAAUUUUAAAAUUUACUUAUGGAUUCUUUCAGAAAACCUGAUUUCAAAUCAGAAAUACUCAUUUUUGCCCCCAGAGCAAAGUUCCAGAAUACUAUUUCUUCUUGAACUUGCCAUUUUCCAUCUGGCUUUGAACUUGAGAAUAGACUCCCCUAUAUUGGCAUAAAAGGUAAAGUGGAAUUUACCACUGAAACUUUCAGAGCUCAAUUUAGUCUGGCCCCAUGGACCAGGCAAGAAUAAACUCUGCUCACCAGUAACAAUUCUGCAGCCACCGUACUGAACACAAACCCUGGAGAAAUUCUGGACAUGGUACUGCUUAAGAAUGCUGGGUACUCGGGAGGCUGAGGCAGGAGAAUGGCGUGAACCCGGGAAGCGGAGCUUGCAGUGAGCCGAGAUUGCGCCACUGCAGUCCGCAGUCCGACCUGGGCGACAGAGCGAGACUCCGUCUCAAAAAAAAAAAAAAAAAAAAAAAAAAGAAUGCUGGGAAUGUCAGUCGAGGGUCUGAUUUCAGAAAGAGGACAUUAAUAUUCAAAUCCCUGAACCAUGCCCACACUGUGGGAGUCAGGCCUAACAAGAUCCCAGGGUCCAUAGUUUACCUGGUCAGCUUGCUGUGUCUCAUGGGGCAUUAGAGGGUAGAUGAGAACUUUCCGCAAUCUCGACAACUGCACUGUAAGAAUUUCUUCUGUGUAUUUUCUAAUUCUGUGACAACAGGCAUCAACAAAACAUGUGGCCUGUUAUCACAUGGUUCCUCCCUGUGUGCACCUUCAUAGAGAUUUUUUCCUUUUCUAAAAGAAUGAGGAUUCCUCUGAAUGUUACACUAUGCAACAAUAAUGUCCCCAGUCCUUCAUAAGUAACACAGUAACAAUAUAAGCACCCUCUCCCUACAUAACACACACACAUACACACAAAUACACACACAGACACAUGCAUACACACACACAUACACACAGACACAUGCAUACACACACAUACAGAGACAUGCGCAUACACACACACGCAUACAUGCACAUGCAUACACACACCAAGACAUGCAUACACACACGCAUACACAGAGACACAUGCAUACACACACGUGCAUACACACACAGACAUAUGCAUACACACACGCAUACAGACAUGCAUACACACACAUGCAUACAGAGACACAUGCAUACACACACGCAUACACACACACGCAUACACAGAGACAUGCAUACACACAUGCAUACAGAGACACAUGCAUACACGCACACAGACACAUGCAUACACACACACGCAGACACAGACACAUGCAUACACACAGAGAUACACGCAUACUCACACAGACACAGACACAUGCAUACGCACACACAGAUAUACACACACACACACACACACACACUCUUAUCCUUUCCAAUCAGUUAUGAGUGACACCACAAAAGUAAAUUUCCAGAAAUCAAAGCCUUAAGAUUGGCGUUCCUCCCCUGCAUGCACUGUGGCAUUAUUUUAAAAAUGUACCAUACACUUCCCUGAACCUGCAGGCAACAGCCUUUCUUCCAGUGUUUGGUAGGAACCCUGGAUUCAGAAGACCAGGUUUUGCCCCCAGAUGAGCAAUGUCGUCCUGGGUAUAUCAUUUCACUGGUCGGAAAUAGCUUCCUCCACCCCUUUUUUAAAAACUUGAUAAAUUUUAUUUUUUAGAGCAGCAUUAACUUCACAGCAAAAUAGAGCAGAAAUUACCAAGAGCUCUCAUUUACCCCCGGCCCCCGCAUGCAUGGCCGCCCCCACGAGUGAUAUGCCAAACCACAAUGGUACAUCUGUGGAAAUGGAUGAGUCUACACUGAGACAUUACUAUCACCCCAGAGUCCAUUGUUUACAAUGGUGUUGUACAUUCUAUGGAUUUGGGCAAAUGUAUAAAGGCAUGGAUCCACCAUUAUAGAAUCAUACAGGAUAGUCCCACGGCCCUAAAAAUCCUCUGUGCUCUCCCAAUUCAUCUUGUGUCCUCCCAACCCCUGGCAACCACUGAUCUAUUUACUGUCUCCAUAGUUUUGCCUUUUCCAGAAUGGCAUAUAAUUGGACUCAUGCAGUACGCAGCCUUAUAAAAUUGGCUUAUUUCACUUAGUAACAUGCAUUUAAGUUUCCCUCAUAUCUUUUUAUGGCUUGAGAGCUCACUUUUUUAGCACCAAACACUCAUCCAUUUUCUGGAUGUACCACUGUUUAUUUAUCCAUUCACCUACUGAAGGACACCUUGGUUGCUUCCAAGUUUGGUCAGUUAUGAAUAAAGCCACUAUAAAUAUCUGUAUGCAGGUUUUUGUGUGGACAUAAGUUUUCAAUUCAUUUGGGUAAAUAUGAUAUGUUAAAGCUAUAUUUAGUCUUGCAAGACACAGCCAAACUGCCUUCCAAAGUGGCUGUACUGUUUUGCAUUCCACUAGCGAUGAAUGAGGGUUCCCGUUGCUCCAUAUCUUCACCAGCAUUUAGUGUUGUCAAUGAUCUGCAUUUGGGCCAUUCUAAAAGAUGUACGGUGGUGUUUCAUUGCUGUUUUAAUUUGCAAUUCCCUAAUGACAUGAUUUGGGACAUAUUUUUAUAUGCUUGUUUUCCAUCUGUACAUCUUCUUUGGUGAGGUGUCUGUUCAGGUCUUUUGGGCAUUUUUUUAAAUCGGGUUGUUUUCUUAUUGUUGAUUUGUUAAAGUUCUUUGUAAAUUUUAGAUAAUAAUUCUUUAUCAGAUGUGUCUUCUGUAAAUAUUUUCUCCCAGUCCGUGGCUUGUCUUCUCAUUAUCUUGACCUUGUCUUUUUCAGAGCAGACGCUUUUAAUUUUACUGAAGUUCAGCUUAUCAUUUACUUCUUUCAUGAUCAUGUCUUUGGUGUUCUAUCUAAAAAUCUAUUGCCAUAUCCAAGGUCAUCUAAGUUUUCUCUUAUAUGUUACCUUCUAGGAGUUGUAUAGUUUUGCAUUUUACAUUAGAUCUGUGACCGAUUUUGAGUUAAUUUUUGUGAAAAGUGUUUGUUAGGUCUGUAUUUAGACUCUUUUUUUUUUUUUUUUUUUUGCCUGUGGAUGUGCAAAUGUGCAGCUAUUUCAACACCGUUUGUUGAAAAGACCCUCUUUGCCGCACUGUUUUGCCUGUGCUCCUUUGCCAAGGAUCAGUUAACUAUAUUUGUGUGGGUCUGUUUCUCAGCUCUCCAUUCUGUUCCACUGAUCUAUUUGUCUAUUCCUUCACCAACACCACAUCGUCUUGAGUACUGUAGCUUUCUUUCUCCAUAUAAACUGCAGACUCAGUUUUUUGGUACCAACAAAAUAACUUGCUGAGAUUUUUAUUGGGAUUGUAUUUAAUCUACAGAGGAAGCUGGGAAGUGACAUCUUGACAAUAUUGAGUCCCUCCAUGAAAUGGAAUAUCUCUGUAUUUACUUAGUUCUUCUUUGAUAUCAUUCACCAGUUUUGUAGUUUUCCUCAUGUAGAUCUUAUACAUAUUGUUAGAUUUAUACCUUAAGUACUUCAUUUCAAGGGAUACUAAUUUAAAUAAUCAUGUGCUUUUAAUUUCAAAUUUCACUUAUUCAUUGCCGGUAUAUAGGAAAACAAUUGACUUUGUAUAUUAACUUUGAAUCCUAAAAUCUUGCUAUAAUCCCUUAUUAGUUCCAGGAAGGUUCUGGGGCUUGUUUUUGUUUUGUUUUUUGGUCAGUUAUUUCAGAUUUUCUACAUAGAUGAUCAUGUCAUCUGUAAACAAAGACAAAGUUUUAUUUCUUCUUUCUUCCCAAUCUAUAUAUUUUUAUUUCCUUUCCUUGUCUUAUUGCAUCAGCCAGGACUUCCAGUAUCAUGUUGAAAAGCAGUAGUGAUGGGGACACCUUUUUUUUCCUGAUCUUAGUGAGACAGCUUCAGGUUUCUCACCAUCACGCCAUUUAGUAUGAUGUUAGCUGUAAGGUUUUUUUUUUAGAUAUUGUUUAUCAGGUUGAGGGGCUUCUCCUCUAUUCCUGCUUUACUGAGUGUUUUUAUCAUGAAAGACUGUUUGGAUUUUUCUGCAUCUGUUGAUAUGAUCAUGCAAUUUUUCUUCUUUUGCCUGUUGAUAUUCAUUACAUUAGUUGAUCUUUGAAUGUUGAACCAGCCUUAUAUACCUAGGACAAAUUCCACCUGGUCAUGGUGUUUAAUUAUUUUCAUAUAUUGUUGGACUUGAUUUGCUAAUAUUUUGUUGAGGAUUUCUGCAUCUAUGCUUAUGACAGGUAUUGGUCUGUAGUUUUCUUGUAAUGUCUUUGUCUGGUUUUGGUAUUAAGGUGAUGCUGGAUUCAUAGAAUGAGUUAGCAAGUGUUCUCUCUGCUUCUAGCUUUUGAAAGAGAUUGUAGAUAAUCAGUAUCAUUUCUUCCUUAAGUCUUUGGUAGAAUUCACCAGUGAACCCAUCUGGGCCAAGUGCUUUCUGGUUGGGGAGGUUACUAACCAUUGAUUCAAAUUAUUUAACAGAGAUAUACCUAUUCAGAUUGUCUAUUUGCUCUUGUGUGAGUUUUGACAAAUUCUAUUUUUCAAGGAAUUGGUUCAUUUCAUCUACAUUAUCAAAUUUGUGGGUAUAAAGUCAUUCAUAAAAUUCCUUCAUUAUCUUUUAUUAUCCUUUUAACCUCCAUGGGAUUGCUAGUAACGUCCCCGCUCUCAUUUCUGAUAGUAGUAAUUUGUGUUCUUUCUCUUUUUUUCUUAGUUAGCAUGCCUUGAGACUUAUGGAGCUUAUUGAUCUUUUCAAAGAAUCAACUUUGUUUCUAUUUAUUUUAUUGAUUUCCUAUUUUCAAUUUCGUGAAUUUUUAAUCUAAUUUUAAUUAUUUCUUCUCAUUGGCUUACUUUGGGUUUAAUUUGCUCUUUUUUUCUACUUUUUUAAAAUGGAAACUUAAAUGAUUGAUUUCAGAUCUUCUUUUGUGCUAUCUGCAUUCAAUGUUAUAAAUUUCCCUUUAAGCAUUGUUUUUAUUGCAUCCCACAAAUUAUAAUAAGCUAUGUUUUUAUUUUCAUUUAUUUCAAAAUAUUUUUUCACUUAUCUUGAGAUUUCUUCUUUGACCCAUGAUAUUUACACGUGUGUUGUUUAAUCUCCAAGUAUUUUGGCAUUUUCCAGCUACCUUUCUGUUACUGAUUUCUAGCUUAAUUCCAUUGUUAUCUAAGAGCAAACAUUGUAGGACUUGUAUUCCUUUUUUUUUUUUUUUUUUUUUUAAGACAGAGUCUCACUCUGUUGCCCAGGCUGGAGUAGAGUGGCAUGAUCUUGGCUCACUGCAACCUCUGCCUCCGGGGUUCAAGCGAUUCUCCUGCCUCAGCCUCCCAAGUAGUUGGGACUACAGGUGCCCACCACCAAACCUGGCUAAUUUUUGUAUUUUUAAUAGAGAUGGGGUUUCAGCAUGUUGGCCAGGCUGGUCUUGAACUCCUGAUCCCAAGUGAUCUGAGAAUUUCUAUUCUUUUAAAUGUGUUAAGGUAUGUUUUAUGACCCAGAAUGCAGUCUAACUUGAUGAACAUUCCAUGCAAGCUUAAGCAAAAAGACUAAUCUGCUGUAGUUUCCUCAUCUUUUUCAACAAACAUUUGAACCCCAUAGUCUCUGCUUUAAUAAUUCUAGUAUCCAUUCCAACCUACACCACCAUCAGUUCUAGACUGUACCUCUACACUAAAUGACCCCAGAUGGUUCAGCUUUAAGUCUCAGCUGUUUUCAUCAUUUAACUGAUUCCCUUGCUGGCAGCAGGGAAAUUAACUACCAGCCACACACUUGUCUCCAACAGCACCCACCGACCACGUCCUGCUCCCCUGUCAUUACCACCACUAAACCCGGUAGCAGAGAGAUGAGCUGUGAGGUAGGUGCCUUCUAGAUAAAUGAGGUGCUACUGGACAUGCACUGUGGUCUUCUCUGCAGUAGAAAAAUGUCCAAGGAAGGUCAGCAUCAUUGAUAGAAAAUAAAUGUGAGGCUGCAUCUCGCCAGCUCAUCCAUGAGCAAUUCCUUCAGCUCCAGCAGGCUACUGACAAUUUGCUUUUAACCCAAAUCCAGCUCUACCCUCCCUAAAGCAUGCACCUAGGGCCCCAGUCAGAAAAACAAAACAAAAACUAAACCAGACAGGAUAAUUAAGGAGGCAAAAAGCUUAAACCAUAAUAUUUUAAUUAAGCUGAUUUAUUUUAACCGUAGCACUACUGCUUUAUUUUAGUUAUAUACCAGUAAUGGAAAAUAGUGGCCACUUUUCAUUAUUAAUCAUAAGAUAAUUCAUUGUAUUUGUCUUUCCUAAUAAAAUGGCAUUAUAUUAAGGCCCAAAAUGUUUACUAUGGCCCAGUAAAAUAUAGGGUUGUUCUGUGAGCUAUUUCUUAGGAUAGAAAAUUAUUCCAGAAAGCUAUUAGUUCAAAAGUCUCUAGCAGUGCCAAGGUUUCAAUAGUCUCUUUAAUUUUGAAUCUAUGCGAUUGAAGAUAAGACUGCAUCUAGUUUGGGGGUUGCAUGUUUGUGGACAUUCAUGUUUCUAUGUACCUGGAACUUCUUAUUCUCACCAUCACACAGAAUUUUCAAGAACUAGUUAAGCAAAGAAAGCAAAGCCCAGCAGGUGUCAGAAUUGGGUCCCCAAGCUGAGGGUCAUUAGGGUGCAUGUCAGUGUGCCAACUCCAAUAUCCACACCUAGAGAACGCACAUCUUCCCAAAAGAAAUGAAGCACAGAUGAUACUUGAUCCUCAACUUUGUCUCCAGAAAUUUUUUCAGGAACUUGAGUUCUUUAUCAAAUGCUCACAUCCUACAGAGAAAUAAAGUGUUCCAUUUUCAAGGUUCAUGAAGCUCGUCAAUGCUGGGAGCAGGCACACACUUGUAUUUUUAUACUCAGGGAUCCCAACAGGCAACUAAAACUAGACAAGGACAAAACUCCACUCAAAAUAUUCUGAAAGUUAGCUGAUGCCCCAUAUUUUAUUACUCCAAAUGUGUAUUCACUUGCCUGAGUGCUGGCCAUGAGCACUCAGUGAACACUUGCAGUACAGUGAGUGAUGUCCUUGACAAGUUACUAUGAAGACUCUGAGAAAAAGUAACAUCCCCCACUGUCCUCAACAAGCCUGUAAUCCCAUGGCUGCCAGCCCUUACCAUGCAACAACACUGCGCUAAGUGCAUCGAACCACACAAAACCCUGUGAGAAAAUACUGCUUCCCACUUCACACGUGAAGUAACUGAGUCUAGUUUUAGAAAUACCUAAACGAAGAGGGACAGGCACAACAAAUUUGCUGGAAUGUAAAGAAAGUAGAUCAGUUUCUGCGUAAGCAGUAAGAAAUGGCCUCAUGAGGAAGAAAGGGACAUUUGCCCUGACAUUUCUCAAAGACUGCUUAGGUUUUGGAGACAGAGAUCCAAGGGCAGGCAAGCACAAUGGUUCAUGCCUGUAAUUCCAGCACUUUGAGAGGCCAAGGUGGGAGGAUUGCUUGAGCCCAGGAAUUCAAGAUUAGCCUGUGCAACACAGCAAGACCCCAUCUCUAUUUUAAAAAGAGAGAGAGAGAUCCAAAAGCAAAGGCAUUUCAGUUUGCAAGGCCAGCAUGGGAGAGGGUCUUAAAACAGAAACACACAAGGUAAGAUUGGGGGAUGGUACCUAGACCAGCCUAGGAUCAUAGGAUUUGAUAAAAUAUGCAUUUGGAAAACUGGUGCUAAUUUAUAGAGACUUAGAAUUUCAGGCUAAGGACAAGGACUAAGAAACGAAUAGCAUGAACAGUAUUAUUGAUAAACCCAUCAUUGCAUCUUAAAGGCUCUGAAGUCUUUAGUAUUGAAUUAAAAAAUAAUUUUCACUGGACAAAACCAAAAGGUCUUUACACAACUGUCAAGCACUUUGAAAUGAUUCAGCAAAAAGCAGAAUAAAUCACUAGUGGAAUUUCAAUAGCAUGUAGUUGUAAACCAUCAUGUGUCCAGCAAAAUCACAAAACAAGAGUUUAUUUUAGAAGGGACUUAGGGAUAUUAAGAAAUAUAACAUACAAAAUAACUAAAGUUUUCUCCAAGCAAAACCAAUGAUCCUUUAGGGAUGAACAGAAAGAAAACAAGAAAUGCUUCUUUCAAAAGUUGCUACCAAGGCUUCUAAGAUUUCUUUGGAAUAAAGUCACUAAGAUUUGCUUCUGAGGUCAAUCUUGCCAACUUUUCCACCAUGCUUUUUAGGAAGGAACACCAGGUAGGGCUCAAGUACUGGUUUGGCUCCUGUCCCAUUUUUUGGUCCUUUUGUAACUCCCUUUACUCAACUCCAAGUAUGUCUGUGCACGGACAAUGAGACGAAAGCAUGCUCAAUGCGAAAGCACAAAUUAUGUAUUGAGAAAUCACUACAAUGCCAAAUUUUUUUAAAAUAAAAAAAAAAUAUAUAUAUAUAUAUAUAUCUUUAAGAACUCGCUGUGUUAGGGAAACUGUUUACAUAUUGAGGUGUUCCUCUUUUUUUGACUGGAACAAUAAAAGAAAAAUUUGAUAUGG